GCCUCCCAAAGUGCUGGGAUUACAGGCAUGAGCCACCGCGCCGGGCCUAUCAUAUGAAUUUUGAGGGAACACAAACAUGCAGUCUGUAGCAGAUGGUAAUAGGCUGACAUAUUACACUUGUUGAUGUAAAUCUGAUAGGUUUCUUUCUCUCCAAGGACAGCUUUUUAAAUAUUUAACAGUAUCAAUAAUUUUUCAGGUUCUGUGAGAAUUUUAUAAUUUAUAAUUUGCAGACUUAAUGUAUAAUCUAUUUUGUCCUAACAAUUACAAAUAUAUUUUUUAUUUCAGAUUGUAUAUAUUCCUACCAGAUGGAGAUAAUUACAGCUUUAAAAAUUUUUAUUUUUUCAUUUUAUUUCACACAUUGACAUUAAAUUUUUAUGGACACAUAAUAACUGUACAUAUAUAUGGGGUAGAAUGUGAUGUUUUAAUACAUGUACUCAAUGUGUAAUGAUCAAAUCAGGGUAAUUUGCAUAAUGAUUUUUCUGUAGGGAGAAAAUUCAAAAUCUACUCUUCUGGCUAUUUUCAAAUAUAUAAUAUGUUAUUGUUAACUAUACUCAUCCUACUAUGCAAUAGGACACCAGAACUUAUUCCUGGGUUCUACAUCCGUUAAGGCAACCAAGGAUUGGAAAUAUUGGAAAAAAAAAUUGCGUCUGUACUGAACAUGUACAGACUUUUUUCUUGUCCUUAUUCCUUACACAAUAUAGUACAAUAACUAUUUGCAUGACAUUUACAUCGGAUAUUAUGAGUGAUCUAGAGUUGAUAUGAAGUAUAUGGGAGGAUGUGCAAAGGUGAUGUGCAAAUACUAUGUCAUUUUAUAUCAGGGACUUGAGUAUCCUUUGUUACCCUCAGGAGAUCCUGAAACCAGUCCCCCAUGGAUACUGAGGGCUGACUGUAUAGUCCUAUCCUCACGGAACUUUCAUUCUAAUGGGGGAAGACUGACUAUAAACAAAAUAUAUGUAAUAGGUGGUGGUAAGUACCGUGGAGAAGUAACAAACGGGGCAAAGUGAGUUAUACAGCUCCAUUCUUAGAAACCUUGGAGUACUUUUCUUAGUUUAUACUCGUGGUGGUUUCCUUUUGUCUCCUUUAUUACAUGGGACUCUGACAUGUGCCCAUAGCUAGGGUGACAGUAGGAUCUACCCGAUAGUAGGGUGGCAGUAGGAUCUACCCAAAAAGCAUCCUGCUGAUACAGGACCAAAGCAUCCUGUUGUUCUCGAGCCUAUAAAAAGAGCUAAUGGUCUUGCUUCUCUUAACUGUGGCCUCCUACACUGUGUUUUGGAUGAUUGGUGAUGUCUUGGAUAUUCUGUUUCUUUGGAACUUUGAAUAUACAACACUUUACUAGGGAAUUAGCAAUGGAAGCAGAGCAAAGAUGUACAGAGGAAACAAUGCGUAACUCUGAUGGAAUUGAAGUCAUGAGGCAGCAGAGAGCUUAAAUUACAGCUUUAAAAAUUUUUAUUUUUUAGAGGGAAUUUACUUGGGAGUAACAGCAGUAAUAGUUAACGGAGCCAGAAUGCUUGAGUCAUAUAAUUGCAAAGCAGAGUUGGGAGCAACAGAUGCUAAAGAGUAGUUGCUGUAGUUCCUCUGUGGGUCGUAGGAGCAGUUGUCAUAUUACUAUAUAGCUACUGCAUGAAGAAGAGUUCUUAGUGAGGCCUGGGUGAACAGCUCUUCUUAGUAUUCUGUGUGACCCCAUUUGACCUUUUAACAAAUCCCUAAGUAAAUAAAUAGCCCCUCAGGAAAACUAAGUUUUUCUCUGCUGUUUUUUUGCUUGAGAGAGCUAUAACUGUAAUAGACUUAUAUUUCUGAACAUUUUAGUGCUUGCCAAUAUUUGGUAAUAUUUAUGUUUCCUAUAUUUGUAAUGAACAUUCUUCUUCCGGUACAUUUUUUGUUAAAUUAUUGUUUGAUGGAUAAAAGUUCACCUUUUAUUGUAUAAAAUUGACUGAGAUUAAUUUAUACACAUUGACAAUGGGUAAAUAGAAUUUUUCAGAUUAUUAAAAGCUGAAGGAUGCCCACGUAAGCAAAAAAAAAAAAGAAAAAACCAACAAAAAUAAACCCAAACCCCUCAAACAAUUUCGAACACGAAACAUUCUUCUGAUGCCGGCAUCCCUGCUUGCAGGUGUGAAGGGGGCAGGAAUCAGCGAGGUGUCCUGGGCUGAGUCCCCGGAGUGGGAAGAGGUGGCAGGAAGGGGAUCUGAGGAGGAGAACAGGGGUCCUGGUGGUCUGUGCUUCUUCCCAGACACGGGAGCUGUAGAGGAGACCUCUGCAGCAGAUGCUAGGGGGGCCAGUAGGCCCAGGCAGUCUUGGGACUUGGGUCUGUCCUGCUGUGCAUCCAUAGUGGGUGCUUUAGAAACGGGAGGCCCACCCGAAGCCCCUGUUGCAAGUGAGGACAAAGUGUGGGAAGGCCGUGAGGGUCUGCAGUCCGGGAUGGCCUUGUCCUCAACGUGCAGUGCACUGUUGAUGCGCUGGAAUGCCGUCUCUUUUUCCAGGUGCAGGUCUUCAGCCGUGACCCGGUACCCCAGCUCUAAGGGAGGUGGCAGCAUCAAAGGCUCCCCUCGCCUGCGUGGCAGCAGGGGAAUCUUGCGUCUACGGGGCCUAGAGUCCUGGGAUCUGGGGGAGCCACCCGUUGGGGCGAUUGUCUGCCCUGGUGCUGUAUCUGCCCCCUUUUCACACCGUGUGUGACCCGAAGAGACAGCCUGAGGCCUGUCCUCACUCACUGUCUUUGAGUAACUGAGGGUCAGCUGGCAGCGGGAUGAGGCUGGCCCCCUCCUCUGCUUUAGCCCCGGCAAGCCUCCCGUGGAGCUGUAGGAGCUGGAGAUGGCAUUUCGUUUGGUGUUCGAGCUCGUCCAGGAUGUCUGGGAUGUGUGGUUAUAUCUGAUUUCUGAGCUCUGGGCGUGGAGGUCUGUCUGCAGAGGCCCGGGCCUGGGCACAAAGGGAGAGGGGCCUCCAUUGUCCCGCAGGGGCCAAAAUGCAGACCGUGCAUCCCCGGUGACCUCGGGGACCGUUCUCUGAUCAUCAGGAUUUUCUUGGACUCUGGGGUCCUUGUCCUGCUCAGGCAUCCCUGCCCCGCUCUCCUUGAGGGCCCUCAACACUAUCUUCCCUGGACACAAGUCUGGGGACAGCCGGGUGUUGUGGACCCCAAAGGGGUGACUACCUGCUCCUGGGCCCCACAGAGUCCUUGUGCUCAGUGUAGUGGCUGAGCUGGGGGAUGCCCUGGAACUCGGAGCACACAGCACUGGCUUACUGUGGUACCUGUGCAGUGAAAUUGAAGACAGAAUCACCAGGAUGGAACACAGGUCUUGCAGGAUCACUUGAAACCUUCUUAGAGUUGUCUUGACACCAGUGAUGUCGAGUGUCCGGGUGUUUGUAGGAUGGCCUGCCACUCAGUCCAGGGGCAGGAGCAACGGGGAGAUCCCACAAGCAAAGUGAACUGGGGGAUGGGCUGAAGGGGCUCCAGGCAACUGAGCCCUACUCGCAGGUCCUCGGCCUUGGCCCAAACAGGAAUGAGGGGCACAGAGUGCCCGGGUAACCGCUCCUGGGAGCAGUGGGGAACUGUCGGAUACUUGAACUCUCAAGAGCUGGGCUCUGAGCGUCCUCGUCCAGCUGCCAACUUGGCCAAAGGCUAAGCCAGCAGAUUGUUCUGUUGCCGGGCAACGCGACUUCUAAACCUGAGGGAGUGGGCAUGUGAGCACAUAAUGGCACCAGUGACAGAGCGACCAUAAUGGAUGAAUAAGCGCAGCCAGGUACCCGCGCAAGGCACCUGCUGGCAAUGGCAGGAGGCGGACGUGGGGGGUCGUGCAGUAGGUACUGGAGGGAGAGACGUGGGCACAAAGGUCGCGGGAGGAACAGGUGCCCACAAUGGCUGCAUAUUUGCCCGUGGAUCACUGAAGAUUCCUGCUCUCCUGCUGAGGUGGAGACUGCAGUGAGCUGAGAUCGCACCAUUGCACUCCAGCCUGGGCAACGAGUGCAAAACUCAGUCUCCAGAUAAAAAAAAGAAAAAGAAAAAAAAGAGGCCGGGUGUGGUGGCUUAUGCCUAUGAUCCUAGCACUUUGGGAGGUCGGGGUGGACGGAUCACGAGAUCAGGAGUUGGAGGCCAGCCUGGCCAACAUAGUGAAAGCCCGUCUCUAGUAAAAAUACAAAAUUUAGUCAGACAUGGUGGGCAGGAGAGAGCAUGUGCAGGGGAACAUCCAUUUAUAAAACCAUCAGACCUCAUGAGACUUAUUCACUACCAUGAGAACAGCAUGGGGGAAACUGCCUCCAUGAUUCAGUUAUCUCCACCUGGCCCCACCCUUGACACAUGGGAAUUGUUACAAUUCAAGAUGAGAUUUGGGUGCGGACAGAGCCAAACCAUAUAAUUCUUCCCCGGCCCCUCCCAAAUCUCAUGUCCUCAUAUUUCAAAAGCAAUCAUGCCUUCCCCUAAGUCCCCCAAACUCUUAUUUCAGCAUUAACUCAAAAUUCCAUAGUCCAAAGUCUCAUCUGAGACAAGGCAAGUCCCUUCCACCUAUGAGCCUGUAAAAUCAAAAGCAAGUUAGUUAUUUUCUAGAUACACAGGGAUACAGGCAUUGGGUAAAUACACUCGUUUCAAAUGGGAGAAAUUGGCCAAAGCGAAAGAGCUACAGGCCCCAUGCAAGUCCAAAACCCAGCAGGCAAAUCUUAAAGCUCCAAAAUGACCUCCUUUGACUCCAUGUGUCACAUCUAGGUGAUGCAAGAAGUGGGUUCCCAGGGUCUUGGGCAGCCCCGCCCCUGUGGCUUUGCAGGGUACAGCCCCCCUUCUGGCUGCAUUGAGUGUCUGCAGCUUUUCCAGGCACACAGUGCAAGCUGUCAGUGGAUCUACCAUUCUGGGGUCUGGAGGAUGGUGGCCCUUUUCUCACAGCUCUGCUUGGCAGUACCCCAGUGGGGACUCUGUGUGGGAGCUCCAACCCCAUAUUUCCCUUUGACACUGCCCUAGCAGAGGUUAUCCAUGAGGGCCCCCCCUCCCCUCCCCCCCACAGCAAACUUUUGCCUGGAUUUCCAGGCAUUUUCAUACAUCUUCUGAAAUGUAGGCGGAGGUUCAUGAACGUUAAUUCUUGACUUCGGUGCAUCUGCAGGCUUAACACCACCUAGAACCUGAAAGGCUUGGAACUUGCACCCUCUGAAGCCAUGGCCUGAGGUGUACCUUGGCCCCUUUUACCUAUGGCAGGAGCAGCUGGGAUGCAGGGCCUCAAGUUCCUAGGCUGCACACAGCAGGGGGUUCUGGACCCACAAAACCAUUUUUCCUUCUAAGCCUCCUGGCCUGCGAUGGGAGGGUCUGCUGUGAGGGUCUCUAACAUGCCCUGGAGACAUUUGCCCCAUUGUCUUGGUGAUUAACAUUUGGCUCCUCAUUACUUAUGCAAAUUUCUACAACCCAGUCUCCUGAGAAAAUAGAUUUUUCUUUUCUGUUGCAUCAUCAGGCUACAAAUUUUCUGAAAUUGUAUGCUCUGCUUCUUCUCGAAUGCUUUGCUGCUUAGAAAUUUCUUGUGUCAGAUACCUUAAAUCAUCUCUCUCAAGUUCAAAGUUCCACAGAUCUGUAGGGAACUCUAGAAAAAAAUUCUUAUUUUCCCUCUUUCCCGCCUAUCUGAUGCCCGUUUCUAAUACAGGUGCACAAUGCCUGCAGUGUCUUUGCAUAGUAAGAGUGACUUUACUCCAUUUCCCAACAAAUUCCUCAUCUCCCUCUGAGACCACCUCCGCCUGGACCUUGUUGUCCAUAUCACUAUUAACAUUUUGGUCAAAGCCAUUCAACAAGUCUCGAGGAAGUUCCAAACUUUCCCACAUUUUCCUAUCCUCUUCUGAGCCUUCCAAACUGUUCCAGCCUCUCCCUGUUACCCAUUUCCAAAGUUGCUUCCACAUUUUCGGGUAUCUUUACAGCAGCACCCCACUCUACUGGUAUCAACUUAUUGUAUUAGUCUGUUCUCACACUGCAAAUAAAGACAUACCUGAGACUGGGUAAUUUAUAAAGGAAAGAGGUUGAAUUGACUCACAGUUCUGCAUGGCUGGGGAGGCCUCACAAUCAUGGUGGAAGGCAAGGAGGUGCAAAAGCAUGUCUCACAUAGUGGCAGGCAGGAGAGAGCAUGUGCAGGGGAGCUCCCAUUUAUAAAACCAUCAGAUCUCAUGAGACUUAGUCACUACCGCGAGAACAGUAUGGGGGGAACCAUCCCCAUGAUUCAGUUAUCUGCACCCGGCCCCACCCUUGACACGUGGGAAUUAUUACAAUGCAAGGUGAGAUUUGGGUGGGGACCCAUCCAAACUAUGUCAGUAUGUUUUGACUUCUUGCUUGAUUGCUAGGUUGCAUAGAGGACAAACAUGGAAAUUAAUGAAGUACCUUAAUAUCUGGCUUCAGAUCUUAGACAGGAUCAGAGGGCCAGCUCAAAUUUGCAAGGAGGGGAGGUAGAUCCCACCAUUUUAUGGGUGAAUGGCAAAAUCAAACAGAAAUUAUGUGGGAUGGGAGAUACUGAUGCAGCCAUCUUUGGAAACAUUCUACUUAGCUAAUUUUAUGCUAGGCUUUAGGUCAAGAAGGAGAGAGAGAGCUGACAUGCUGUGGUACACACUUAUAGUCCCAGCGACUUGGAAAGCUGAGGCAGGAGGAUUGCUUGAUCCCAGGAGUUUGAGGUAGUGUGCGAUGAUCGUUCUUGUGAAUAGCCACUAGCCACCGAACUCCAGCUUGGGCAACAUUGAGACACCCUGUCUCUUAAUUUAAAAAAAAAAAAAAAAAAAGGAGGAAAGAAAGUGGUCUCAGUUUUUAAUGUAAAUAUUUUUAAUGGGAUACUGAUAUUUUAAGAUUAAUGUAUAUUGUAUAUCAGUUAACUGCAGGUCAAUAAUUAUAUAAAACUUAAGGUACGAAAAACAUUUAUUUUUGCUAACAUAUCUGUGAGUUGACUGUUGUUGGCUUGGUGAGGCUGCAAGCUGCAGAUAGAGUCUAGGUAUGUUUUCUGUGUGUUUGUUCCCCCUUGGAUCAGUGGACUACCUGAGAAUGUGUUUCUGUCACAGUGAUAGAAUCACAAGGAAACUCCAGUUCUGGAAGUACAUUUUAAGCCAUUGCUUCUCUCAUGUCCACUAACAUUCAGUCAGCCAAAGCACAUACCUUGUCCAUGGCUAACAUUGAUAGUAUAGAUAAAUAUACCUGAUCUCUAGCAGGAGGAACUGCAUUGUCUUGGGGAAAGGUUUUAGAUAUAGGGAGGGGUGAUGAGUUGGGAACAAUAAUGUAGUCUGCCGCAAACAUAUUAAAGUGUAACUGGAUAUGGUUGCUGCAGAAUUUUGAACCUUUGUUUUAAUUGUGAUUUUUACUCUUUCCCCCCUAUCUAGUGCCCUUUUGUAAUACAGUAAUUAUCAUGAUUUUUGUCUGAACUGAAAUCUUCUGAGAUUAGAUUGUCUACGAAAAUACAGUCGAUCCUCCUUGUUUUCAGCUUUUGUAUUUGUGAACUCACCUACUAUUUUUUGUAACCCCCAAAUCAGUACUCACAGCACUUUCAUAGUCAUGUGUUUGCGCAGAGUGUCAAAGAAUUUGAGUUUGAACAGGAUGAUAUUCUGCCUUCUUUUUCAGCUCUCAUACAAUAGUCAGGUAUCCUUUUUGUGGUCUAUUUAAUGCCAUGCUUUUCCUGUUUUUGUACUGUUUGUUGGUUGUUUUGCCAUUUAAAUUAACCCCCAAGCAUAGUGCUGAAGUGCUGCUUAGCAUUCACAAGUCCAAGAAGUCUGUGAUGUGUCUUACAGAGAAAAUACAUGCAUUAAAUAAACUCCAUUCAGGCGUGAGUGCUGUAGUGCCGUUGGCUGUGAGUUCAAUGUUAAU